GCCGCCAUCUUGUCCGCCAUUUGCAAGGGGCCCGGAGCGGGAUCGCGGCACCUGCCGAGCGGGUCGCCGCCUCUGCCGCGGUCCUUGGACCCCGCCGCCGCCCUGGCCUGGGAGCUUGCCCCGCCGCAGCGGCCGGCAGCGCGGCGCUCCGCGGGCGGCAGGCACGGGCCCCGGGCCCCCUCACGGCGCCCAGCCGCGGGCCUCCCGAGGCAAAAGCCCGUGGGCCGCCGCGAUGGCCCUCAAGAUGGUGAAGGGCAGCAUCGACCGCAUGUUCGACAAGAAUCUGCAGGACUUGGUCCGCGGCAUCCGUAACCACAAGGAGGACGAGGCAAAAUACAUAUCUCAGUGCAUUGAUGAGAUCAAGCAGGAGCUGAAGCAGGACAACAUAGCGGUGAAGGCGAACGCGGUCUGCAAGCUGACGUAUUUACAGAUGUUGGGAUACGACAUCAGCUGGGCCGCCUUCAACAUCAUAGAAGUGAUGAGUGCCUCCAAGUUCACCUUCAAGCGAAUUGGCUACCUCGCUGCUUCCCAGAGCUUUCACGAAGGCACCGACGUCAUCAUGCUGACCACCAAUCAGAUCCGUAAGGACUUGAGCAGCCCCAGCCAGUACGACACAGGUGUUGCACUGACGGGUCUGUCCUGCUUCGUCACCCCAGACCUUGCCAGAGACCUGGCAAAUGACAUCAUGACACUGAUGUCACACACCAAGCCCUACAUCAGGAAGAAGGCUGUGCUGAUCAUGUACAAGGUGUUCCUGAAGUACCCCGAGUCGCUGCGCCCUGCCUUUCCCCGGCUGAAGGAGAAGCUGGAGGACCCCGACCCCGGGGUUCAGUCGGCUGCCGUCAAUGUCAUCUGCGAGCUGGCCAGACGCAACCCUAAGAACUACCUGUCCCUGGCCCCGCUCUUUUUCAAGCUGAUGACGUCCUCCACCAACAACUGGGUCCUCAUCAAGAUCAUCAAGCUGUUCGGUGCUCUUACUCCUUUGGAACCGCGGCUGGGCAAGAAGCUGAUCGAGCCCCUCACCAAUCUCAUCCACAGCACGUCUGCCAUGUCUCUCCUCUAUGAAUGUGUGAACACCGUGAUUGCAGUGCUCAUCUCGCUGUCCUCCGGCAUGCCCAACCACAGCGCCAGCAUCCAGCUUUGUGUUCAGAAAUUAAGGAUAUUGAUCGAGGACUCCGAUCAGAACUUGAAGUACCUGGGGCUGCUGGCAAUGUCCAAGAUCCUGAAGACCCACCCCAAGUCCGUGCAGUCCCACAAGGACCUCAUCCUGCAGUGCCUGGACGACAAGGACGAGUCCAUCCGGCUGCGGGCCCUGGACCUGCUCUAUGGGAUGGUGUCCAAGAAGAACCUGAUGGAGAUCGUGAAGAAGCUGAUGACCCACGUAGACAAGGCAGAGGGUACCACCUACCGUGACGAGCUGCUCACCAAGAUCAUUGACAUCUGCAGCCAGUCCAACUACCAGUACAUCACCAACUUCGAGUGGUACAUCAGCAUCCUGGUGGAGCUGACCCGGCUGGAGGGCACACGGCACGGCCACCUCAUCGCCGCCCAAAUGCUGGACGUGGCCAUCCGCGUGAAGGCCAUCCGCAAGUUCGCCGUGUCCCAGAUGUCUGCGCUGCUUGACAGUGCACACCUGCUGGCCAGCAGCACCCAGCGGAACGGGAUCUGUGAGGUGCUGUACGCUGCCGCCUGGAUCUGCGGGGAGUUCUCAGAGCAUCUGCAGGAACCACACCACACUUUGGAGGCCAUGCUGCGGCCCAGAGUCACCACGCUGCCAGGCCACAUCCAGGCCGUGUAUGUGCAGAACGUGGUCAAGCUCUACGCCUCCAUCCUGCAGCAGAAGGAGCAGGCCGGGGAGGCAGAGGGCGCUCAGGCCGUCACCCAGCUCAUGGUGGACCGGCUGCCCCAGUUUGUGCAGAGCGCAGACCUGGAGGUGCAGGAGCGGGCGUCCUGCAUCCUGCAGCUGGUCAAGCACAUCCAGAAGCUUCAGGCCAAGGACGUGCCUGUGGCAGAGGAGGUCAGCGCUCUCUUUGCUGGGGAGCUGAACCCAGUGGCCCCCAAGGCCCAGAAGAAGGUUCCAGUCCCCGAAGGCCUGGACCUGGACGCCUGGAUCAAUGAGCCACUCUCGGACAGCGAGUCAGAGGACGAGAGGCCCAGGGCCGUCUUCCACGAGGAGGAGCAGCGGCGUCCCAAGCACCGGCCGUCGGAGGCGGACGAGGAAGAGCUGGCUCGGCGCCGAGAGGCCCGGAAGCAGGAGCAGGCCAACAACCCCUUCUACAUCAAGAGCUCGCCAUCGCCACAGAAGCGGUACCAGGACACCCCGGGCGUGGAGCACAUUCCCGUGGUGCAGAUUGACCUCUCCGUCCCCUUGAAGGUUCCAGGGCUGCCUAUGUCAGAUCAGUAUGUGAAGCUGGAGGAGGAGCGGCGGCACCGGCAGAAGCUGGAGAAGGACAAGAGGAGGAAAAAGAGGAAGGAGAAGGAGAAGAAGGGCAAGCGCCGCCACAGCUCGCUGCCCACGGAGAGCGACGAGGACAUCGCCCCUGCCCAGCAGGUGGACAUCGUCACAGAGGAGAUGCCUGAGAAUGCUCUGCCCAGCGACGAGGAUGACAAAGACCCCAACGACCCCUACAGGGCUCUGGAUAUUGACCUGGAUAAGCCCUUAGCCGACAGCGAGAAACUGCCUAUUCAGAAACACAGAAACACCGAGACCUCAAAAUCCCCUGAGAAGGACGUUCCCAUGGUAGAAAAGAAGAGCAAGAAACCCAAGAAGAAAGAGAAAAAACACAAAGAGAAAGAGAGAGACAAGGAGAAGAAGAAGGAGAAGGAGAAGAAGGCUGAGGACCUGGACUUCUGGCUGUCUACCACCCCACCGCCUGCCCCCGCCCCCGCCCCCGCCCCCGUUCCAUCCACGGGGGAGCUCAGUGUGAACACUGUCACUACCCCGAAGGACGAGUGUGAGGACGCCAAGACGGAGGCGCAGGGCGAGGAGGACGAUGCCGAGGGGCAAGACCAGGACAAGAAAUCUCCCAAGCCUAAGAAGAAGAAGCACAGGAAGGAGAAGGAGGAGCGGACCAAAGGCAAGAAGAAGUCCAAGAAGCAGCCUCCAGGCAGCGAGGAGGCAGCGGGGGAGCCGGUGCAGAAUGGCGCGCCAGAGGAGGAGCAGCUCCCGCCUGAGUCCAGCUACUCCCUCCUCGCUGAAAAUUCCUAUGUUAAAAUGACCUGUGACAUCCGGGGCAGUCUGCAGGAGGACAGCCAGGUCACUGUGGCCAUCGUGCUGGAGAACAGGAGCAGCAGCAUCCUCAAGGGCAUGGAGCUCAGCGUGCUGGACUCACUCAAUGCCAGGAUGGCCCGGCCGCAGGGCUCCUCCGUCCACGAUGGCGUCCCCGUGCCUUUCCAGCUGCCCCCAGGCGUCUCCAACGAAGCCCAGUAUGUGUUCACCAUCCAGAGCAUCGUCAUGGCGCAGAAGCUCAAGGGGACCCUGUCCUUCAUUGCCAAGAAUGACGAGGGUGCGACCCACGAGAAGCUGGACUUCAGGCUGCACUUCAGCUGCAGCUCCUACUUGAUCACCACUCCCUGCUACAGUGACGCCUUUGCUAAGUUGCUGGAGUCUGGGGACUUGAGCAUGAGCUCAAUCAAAGUCGAUGGCAUUCGGAUGUCCUUCCAGAAUCUUCUGGCGAAGAUCUGUUUUCACCACCAUUUUUCCGUUGUGGAGCGAGUGGACUCCUGCGCCUCCAUGUACAGCCGCUCCAUCCAGGGCCACCAUGUCUGCCUCCUGGUGAAAAAGGGUGAGAACUCUGUCUCAGUCGACGGGAAGUGCAGUGACUCCACGCUACUGAGCAACUUGUUAGAAGAGAUGAAGGCGACGCUGGCCAAGUGUUGAGAGCUGCCUGCGAGCCCCGCACCACCCCGCGGAGCACGUACCCAGGGACCGCAGCCCUGACGUGUCUCGCCUCUCCUCAGUCGUGUGUACUGUACCCAAGCCUGAGUGUUAAUUUAACUCUAUGUUGUCCGCCGUGUAGACAUCCGAGGUCAUUUGUUGCGUUGAAUUAUCUGACCAUCCUUUUUUACUGUGACUCUUCCCAUUCUCUUUGGCAAGAAGUCCCCUUCUCGCCCCCAAACCAGCAAGGGACUCCCCCACCUGGGUCUGUGCCCUGCCCCGCGCUGGGGGCCGAGUCCUUGAAUGUGGCUUCAGGGGCUCCUGUCCUGGGCCAGGGCCUGAUGGGCACCACGUGAGGGGCACUUGGUGGACAGGGCGGGGCUGACGUGGCCUCCUCUGGGGUCGCCUGCUUUUGACCCAAAGGUCCUGACGGUUGCGUCCGGGGGAGGGGAAGGAAGGGCCGCUGUCGCCAAGGUUUUCUCUCCCAGAACCCACAGUGGGAAAGCGGUCUUGCCAGGCGUUGUCCAUUGUCAGUGUGCUCGUGGGCUGGUGACUGGGUCUUGGGAUCCCAGGCCACGCGCCAGCCAGGCUGUGGGCAGGGCGGGGCCAGGGACGCCAAAGAGAGGUUGCAGUCAGAACCGUGGACGGGGUGGGUUGAGGCCUCUCUGCCACCCGUCUUCCUGGUCAGCAGAAGUGCAUCUCGGCUUGGGUUUGGGGUGGUCCGCAUCCCCUGCUUGCCACUAUGCGCACCAAGGUUUCCCCACAUCCUUCCCAGCACCCUUAGGAAGGCCCAGGCAGGGCCUGGAAGCAGCGGACCUGGGCUGUUCUGUGUUGAAGGAGUGUGCCCAGUGCCCUUGGGCAGGACCUGUGAGAGCCACCUCACAGGCAGAGCCCCCACCAGGCAGGGCAAGGAGACUCCGCUCACUCCCCACGGCCAGCGUGGGCACAGGACUGACCCUUCUUCAGAGAUAAUGACAUUUUAUCUUCUCCUUUUGAUGAAAACUGUCACUUUAGCAUGUAAUCCAUUACAGAAUCCCAUGCAGUGAUUCCAGGAUUUGAAAUUGUAUGAUGUGUUACAUAAGAAUUUAUUUGCUAUCGACAUUCCCGUAUAAAGAGAGAGACAUAUCACGCUGCUGUCAUGAUUUUGUGUCAAGAUGAUCCAAUAAAGUUGUAAAACAGGCAUUUCCA